AUGUGUCCCCUCCCUCUCGCAGCCGCCGCAGUCGCUGCGCCCCGAGCCCCUCUCCGGCUCCUCAACAGAGGGCUCGCCGCCGCCAUGUCUACCGCCCAGUCACUCAAAUCCGUGGACUACGAGGUGUUCGGAAGAGUGCAGGGUGUUUGCUUCAGAAUGUAUACAGAAGAUGAAGCUAGGAAAAUAGGAGUGGUUGGCUGGGUGAAGAAUACCAGCAAAGGCACCGUGACAGGCCAAGUGCAGGGGCCAGAAGACAAAGUCAAUUCCAUGCUGGAGUGCAGUGGUCUGAUCUAGACUCACUGCAGCCUUGACCUUCUGGGCUCAAGUGAUCUUCCCACGUCAACCUCCUGAGUGCACAUGCUGGCUAAUUUGUGUGUGUGUGUGUGUGUGUGUGUGUGUAUAUUUUGUUGUUGUUGUUGUUGUUGUUGUUGUUGUUGCUUUGUAGAGAUAGUGUCUCACUAUGUUGCUCAGGCUGGUAUAGGACUCUUGGCUUCAAAUGACUUUCCUGCCUCAGCCUCCCAAAGUGCUGGGAUUACAAAAAUAAACUUUAUUUUUGAGAACAGUUUUAUAUUUACAGAAAAAUUGUGAAGAUAGUACAGAGACUUUCCAUAUACUCCCCACACAGUUUUCCUCCUAUUAACAUUUUACAUUAAUAUGAUACGUAUGUUAACAAUUAAUGGACCAAUAUGGAUACAUUAGUAUUAACUAAAAUCCCUAUUUAUUUAGAUUUCAAUUUUUACCUAAUGUCCAUUUUAUGUCUUAGGAUCCCAUUAUUGUAUUUGCUUUUUAAUUGGGCAUUCUCUUGAAAUUAAGAGAAGUGACAUUUUGGCUGGGUGCAGUGGCUCAUGCCUGUAAUCCCAGCACUUCGGGAGGCUGAGGCGGGCGGAUCACUUGAGGUCAGGAGUUCAAGACCAGCCUGUCCAACACAGCGAGAUCGUGUCUCUACAAAAAAUACAAAAACUAGCUGGGGUUGGUGGCACACGCCUGUUGUCCCAGCUACUUGGGAGGCUGAGGCAAGAGAAUCGCUUGAGUCUGGGAGGCAGAGGUUGCAAUGAGAUGAGAUUGCACCACCGCACUCCAGUCUGGGCAAUGGGAGUAGCCUGUCCCAAAAAAAAUAAAAUAAAAUAAAAAUAAAGACAGAAGUGACAUUUUUAUGAUAUUAAAUCUUCCCAUUUAAGAACACACAGAUGUUGUUCCAUUUGCUUAGAUUUUAAAAUUUAUCCUUCAGUAUGAUUUUAUGGUUUUCUUUAUAUAGGUUUUUGUACUUUUCUUGCUAAGUUAUUUCUAAGUAUCUUAAUGACUUUUUCACUAUUGCAUAUGGAUUUCUUUCCCAUUUAUGCUUCUAGUUGUUCAUGCUUAAAUAUGGAAUAUCUAAUGACUUUUGUGUAUUAAUUAGAUAUCAUAGUAUUACCUUAUCAGAUAUUCUUAUUAAUUCUAUCAGUUUUUUAAAAAACUAUAGUCUAUUGGGUUUUUAAAAAAUACAGUUAUGCAAUUAGUAAAAAUGGUGUAUCUUUGUUUCAGUGACUUCAUUUGUCAGACCUGCCAUGACAAUGUUGAAUAAUAAUAGCCAUAGCAGGCAUGCCUGUUUGGUUUCUGACUUUAUUUAAAAUAGUUUUAUUGUUUCACCUAGUAAAAAGAUGUUUGCUGUUGGUUUUAGGUAAAUAUACUUUAUCACAAUAAAUUUUACUUUUGCAUUCCUUGAA